GACGCCGGCCAAGACAGCACAGACAGAUUGACCUAUUGGGGUGUUUCGCGAGUGUGAGAGGGAAGCGCCGCGGCCUGUAUUUCUAGACCUGCCCUUCGCCUGGUUCGUGGCGCCUUGUGACCCCGGGCCCCUGCCGCCUGCAAGUCGGAAAUUGCGCUGUGCUCCUGUGCUACGGCCUGUGGCUGGACUGCCUGCUGCUGCCCAACUGGCUGGCAAGAUGAAGCUCUCCCUGGUGGCCGCGAUGCUGCUGCUGCUCAGCGCGGCGCGGGCCGAGGAGGAGGACAAGAAGGAGGACGUGGGCACGGUGGUCGGCAUCGACCUGGGGACCACCUACUCCUGCGUCGGCGUGUUCAAGAACGGCCGCGUGGAGAUCAUCGCCAACGAUCAGGGCAACCGCAUCACGCCGUCCUAUGUCGCCUUCACUCCUGAAGGGGAACGUCUGAUUGGCGAUGCCGCCAAGAACCAGCUCACCUCCAACCCCGAGAACACGGUCUUUGACGCCAAGCGGCUCAUCGGCCGCACGUGGAAUGACCCGUCUGUGCAGCAGGACAUCAAGUUCUUGCCGUUCAAGGUGGUUGAAAAGAAAACUAAACCAUACAUUCAAGUUGAUAUUGGAGGUGGGCAAACAAAGACAUUUGCUCCUGAAGAAAUUUCUGCCAUGGUUCUCACUAAAAUGAAAGAAACCGCUGAGGCUUAUUUGGGAAAGAAGGUUACCCAUGCAGUUGUUACUGUACCAGCCUAUUUUAAUGAUGCCCAACGCCAAGCAACCAAAGACGCUGGAACUAUUGCUGGCCUAAAUGUUAUGAGGAUCAUCAACGAGCCUACGGCAGCUGCUAUUGCUUAUGGCCUGGAUAAGAGGGAGGGGGAGAAGAACAUCCUGGUGUUUGACCUGGGUGGCGGAACCUUCGAUGUGUCUCUUCUCACCAUUGACAAUGGUGUCUUCGAAGUUGUGGCCACUAAUGGAGAUACUCAUCUGGGUGGAGAAGACUUUGACCAGCGUGUCAUGGAACACUUCAUCAAACUGUACAAAAAGAAGACGGGCAAAGAUGUCAGGAAAGACAAUAGAGCUGUGCAGAAACUCCGGCGCGAGGUAGAAAAGGCCAAACGGGCCCUGUCUUCUCAGCAUCAAGCAAGAAUUGAAAUUGAGUCCUUCUAUGAAGGAGAAGACUUUUCUGAGACCCUGACUCGGGCCAAAUUUGAAGAGCUCAACAUGGAUCUGUUCCGGUCUACUAUGAAGCCCGUCCAGAAAGUGUUGGAAGAUUCUGAUUUGAAGAAGUCUGAUAUUGAUGAAAUUGUUCUUGUUGGUGGCUCGACUCGAAUUCCAAAGAUUCAGCAACUGGUUAAAGAGUUCUUCAAUGGCAAGGAACCAUCCCGUGGCAUAAACCCAGAUGAAGCUGUAGCGUAUGGUGCUGCUGUCCAGGCUGGUGUGCUCUCUGGUGAUCAAGAUACAGGUGACCUGGUACUGCUUGAUGUAUGUCCCCUUACACUUGGUAUUGAAACUGUGGGAGGUGUCAUGACCAAACUGAUUCCAAGGAACACAGUGGUGCCUACCAAGAAGUCUCAGAUCUUUUCUACAGCUUCUGAUAAUCAACCAACUGUUACAAUCAAGGUCUAUGAAGGUGAAAGACCCCUGACAAAAGACAAUCAUCUUCUGGGUACAUUUGAUCUGACUGGAAUUCCUCCUGCUCCUCGUGGGGUCCCACAGAUUGAAGUCACCUUUGAGAUAGAUGUGAAUGGUAUUCUUCGAGUGACAGCUGAAGACAAGGGUACAGGGAACAAAAAUAAGAUCACAAUCACCAAUGACCAGAAUCGCCUGACACCUGAAGAAAUCGAAAGGAUGGUUAAUGAUGCUGAGAAGUUUGCUGAGGAAGACAAAAAGCUCAAGGAGCGCAUUGAUACUAGAAAUGAGUUGGAAAGCUAUGCCUAUUCUCUAAAGAAUCAGAUUGGAGAUAAAGAAAAGCUGGGAGGUAAACUUUCCUCUGAAGAUAAGGAGACCAUGGAAAAAGCUGUAGAAGAAAAGAUUGAAUGGCUGGAAAGCCACCAAGAUGCUGACAUUGAAGACUUCAAAGCUAAGAAGAAGGAACUGGAAGAAAUUGUUCAACCAAUUAUCAGCAAACUCUAUGGAAGUGCAGGCCCUCCCCCAACUGGUGAAGAGGAUACAGCAGAAAAAGAUGAGUUGUAGACACUGAUCUGCUAGUGCUGUAAUAUUGUAAAUACUGGACUCAGGAACUUUUGUUAGGAAAAAAUUGAAAGAACUUAAGUCUCGAAUGUAAUUGGAAUCUUCACCUCAGAGUGGAGUUGAAACUGCUAUAGCCUAAGCGGCUGUUUACUGCUUUUCAUUAGCAGUUGCUCACAUGUCUUUGGGUGGGGGGGAGAAGAAGAAUUGGCCAUCUUAAAAAGCGGGUAAAAAACCUGGGUUAGGGUGUGUGUUCACCUUCAAAAUGUUCUAUUUAACAACUGGGUCAUGUGCAUCUGGUGUAGGAAGUUUUUUCUACCAUAAGUGACACCAAUAAAUGUUUGUUAUUUACACUGGUCUAAUGUUUGUGAGAAGCUUCUAAUUAGAUCAAUUACUUAUUUUAGGAAAUUUAAGACUAGAUACUCGUGUGUGGGGUGAGGGGAGGGAGUAUUUGGUAUGUUGGGAUAAGGAAACACUUCUAUUUAAUGCUUCCAGGGAUUUUUUUUUUUUUUUUUAACCCUCCUGGGCCCAAGUGAUCCUUCCACCUCAGUCUCCCAGCUAAUUGAGACCACAGGCUUGUUACCACCAUGCUCGGCUUUUGCAUUAAUCUAAGAAAAGGGGAGAGAAGUUAAUCCACAUCUUUACUCAGGCAAGGGGCAUUUCACAGUGCCCAAGAGUGGGGUUUUCUUGAACAUACUUGGUUUCCUAUUUCCCCUUAUCUUUCUAAAACUGCCUUUCUGGUGGCUUUUUUUAAAAUUAUUACUAAUGAUGCUUUUAUAGCUGCUUGGAUUCUCUGAGAAAUGAUGGGGAGUGAGUGAUCACUGGUAUUAACUUUAUACACUUGGAUUUCAUUUGUAACUUUAGGAUGUAAAGGUAUAUUGUGAACCCUAGCUGUGUCAGAAUCUCCAUCCCUGAAAUUUCUCAUUAGUGGUACUGGGGUGGGAUCUUGGAUGGUGACAUUGAAACUACACUAAAUCCCCUCACUAUGAAUGGGUUGUUAAAGGCAAUGGUUUGUGUCAAAACUGGUUUAGGAUUACUUAGAUUGUGUUCCUGAAGAAAAGAGUCCAGGUAAAUGGUAUGAUCAAUAAAGGACAGGCUGGUGCUAACAUAAAAUCCAAUAUUGUAAUCCUAGCACUUUGGGAGGCCAAGGCGGGUGGAUCACAAGGUCAAGAGAUAGAGACCAUCUUUGCCAACAUGGUGAAACUCCAUCUCUACUGAAAAUACAAAAAUUAGCUGGGCGUGGUAGUGCAAGCUGAAGGCUGAGGCAGGAGAAUCACUCGAACCCGGGAGGCAGAGGUUGCAGUGAGCCGAGAUCACACCACUGUACUCCAGCCCGGCACUCCAGCCUGGCGACAAGAGUGAGACUCCACCUCAAAAAAAAAAAAAAGAAUCCAAUACUGCCCAAGGAUAGGUAUUUUAUAGAUGGGCAACUGGCUGAAAGGUUAAUUCUCUAGGGCUAGUAGAACUGGAUCCCAACACCAAACUCUUAAUUAGACCUAGGCCUCAGCUGCACUGCCCGAAAAGCAUUUGGGCAGACCCUGAGCAGAAUACUGGUCUCAGGCCAAGCCCAAUACAGCCAUUAAAGAUGACCUACAGUGCUGUGUACCCUGGGGCAAUAGGGUUAAAUGGUAGUUAGCAACUAGGGCUAGUCUUCCCUUACCUCAAAGGCUCUCACUACCGUGGACCACCUAGUCUGUAACUCUUUCUGAGGAGCUGUUACUGAAUAUUAAAAAGAUAGACUUCAA